UAAUAUAUUCAAAUGCUUUUCCGUGGAAAACAAAAUUGUGAUUUUUCAGUAUUUAAGGCUUAUAAGUAGAAAAAGCCAAGCUGUAUAAAAAAAAAGCAUCAAUUUUUAAACUCUAAAUAGGUCCUAGCUGUGAAUGACACUAUAAUUUUCUUAUAUCUGAUGAACCCAUUCAUCUGUCUCCAAAAGACAGGAUAAUUGACACCAGACUGAAUACCUGAGCGAGCAUAACUAUUCAGUAACUCAAUCUUAUAACUGGGUGGAUAGAGGCCAUGUUGUAGAUCUUCACAACAGGGAACAACAGGCCUUAAGAUGACUUUCCUCUACAAACAUUACAAUAGGUGAUUUCAAGAAGAUUCCACUGUGAUUCCCAUAGAAAAUCUAAUAAGCUUUUAUUUUGUUUUUGUUUUGUUUUGUUUUUGAGGAGUCUCGCUUUUUCACCCAGGCUGGAGUGCAGUGGUGCGAUCUCAGCUCACUUCAACCUCCACAUCCCGGGUUCAAACAAUUCUCCUGCCUCAGCCUCCCGAGUAGCUGGGAUUACAGGUGCCCGCCACCGCGUUGGCUAAUUUUUGUAUUUUUAGUAGAGACAGGAUUUCACCAUGUUGGCCAGGCUGGUCUCGAACUCUUGACCUCAAGUGAUCCACCCGCCUCAGCCUCCCAAAGUGCUGGGAUUACAGGCGUGAGCCACUGUGCCCAGCCAGUUUAUUUAUUUUCUAAGCAAUGGGCACUCUAUCCAAACUACAGAGACAGUUAAAAUCUUGUAUUGUUGUUGCUGCACUACUUCUGAGUAUCUCACAUUUUCACUGGUAAGUAACUGUCUGGUAAAAUAUUUAUUAAGCACUUAGUUCUCAAACUUGUGACACAGAACACAGGAUGUUAUUAUACAAUAUUUUAACCUCUAAUUUACAUAAGCAAAAAUUUUAAAUAAACAGAUUUGUUUCUCACUGCAAUUUAGACAAAAGUUCACAAACACAAAUGUGAGAAAUGUGAGAUGCUCCAUGAUUCUUGAGAAUUACUGAAUGAUUAUUCAUUUCAGAUAAAUUAUUCAUGUACGGUAUAUAUCGUCAGUUCUAGCUACAGAGAAAAUUAAUCAAAAUAAAUUACUCUAAUUCUUCUCUUUACCAUAUACGUCUCAUUGAUACAACAGACUUAUUUUAUAGUUGUGCAAGCAAUGGAGCACUUAAAGAAACACAUUAUGUUACCAUUAUUAUGUAAUAUUUGAAAUAGAAGUGCGUAAGCCAAAAUCCUAGGGCCUUAGAAAGUAACAAUAAGCAAAGAUGUGACACUAUAUCAAUGCACACGAAUACUAGUUUUUCACAUAAAGAAGAAAAGUAUGUUCAAAAUUCCAAGGUACAAAUGGUAACUAUCCAAAUUCAUGGUCGCCAAGGACAUCGGUAAAGCCUGGAGUAGCUUUCAGAUGUGAGGAGCUUCCUUAAAGCUCUGGAAUAAGCAGGAUUCAGGAAUAGUAAGGAUAAAUGCAGAGCGCUUAGAAGAUGACCAAUAAGAACAGAUCUUAGUCCUGCCUGAACAUGCUGUGAAAGCUUGAGGAACACACCAGUGCCAGCCCUCAAUCUCCUCAACUGACUUGGGGAUUAGACUACAGGCUAUCGAUAAAGUUUCCAUCCAUCCUUAAAAUCCUAUGACUCCAAAAUUUCUAUCACAUGCAAAAGUAUAAAGGCAGGAAGGAACUGUACACAGAAUAAUAGAGACCCCACCAAUCCCAAUCUUAAUCUGGGAUGUAAGUAGAGAUGGUAGAGAGAAACUAGGUUAUGGAAGCUUUGAGAGCAAAGUUGGUUUAAACUUAUUGGAUGGGCCUAGGUUUUGUUUUUAAAUGUGCGUGUGAGAGAGAGAGAGAGAGAGAGAGUGUGUGCACGUGGUUGUAUGCAUAGAACAGCAAAAUAUACGAAAAGCCUAAACUUAUAUUCUUAGUAUUUUGGUAAAAAGUUAAAAAUAGUUUAUUUCAGCUUUAUUACAUAAAAAUUGUUUAGAACAUAGUUCCUGCCCACACAGUAAGCCCUUAGUAAAGACUGGCAGAUAUAAUAAUAAUCAUUAUCAUUUCUAUCAUCAUCUUACUAUUGUUACUGAGGCAGUGUUUUGGAGUGGUUUUGAAUGUGAUUCUGAGAUCAGACUGACUGAGCUGGAAUCCUGGCUUUAUAUCUUACCAGCUACACAACCUUGGGUAAGUAACCCCAUUAUGCCUCAAUUUCCUCAUCUGUAAAGCAGGGACAAUAACAACACCUAGCUUAUGGAAAUGAUAAGAAGUUAAAUAAGUACAUGUAAAGUAUUUGGCAUAGUGCCAGAUACAAACCAACUGCUUAAUUAUUUUCAUCGAGUUUGGUAAAGAAUGACAUUAUUCAUGGACUCUAACGUGCUAACUCAGGUAGGGAAAGAGAAAGGGCAUGUAGCCUUUAAGCAGCACUUGAAUUUAGAAAGCUUUGUGUACAUCUGCCUUAUUCAUCUGUUUGCAUACAUUGUUUCAUUACAAAUGCACACAAAGGAUCAUUAAUUAAUUGGGGAAAUUAAAAUUUAGAAAGAUGUCAGAAGUUUUAUUCUCUUAUUAAAAGGCACUUACAGAGUAGCUGAUCUGGCCUUCAAUGUUGGUCACUAUAACUUAUAUUUGCUUCUUUUAAAAAGGUUGUAUUAUAAUAUAAAAUGUUUCCUUGCUAAAAUACAAAAAUAAUCUUCAGGUCUUUAAAACAAAAGAACACUGUUUAAUGUGCAAAAGGGGGACCCACACCAACAGGCAGCACCAGAAAGAUUACUAAUGUACCCUUAGCUCUAAGCAUGUGAGUUUGAAUAGACCAGGUCAAAGGGAGCCCUAUCAGUUUAACUUGAGCUUACAAACCCGCUCAAUGUUCCAGAUUUGGGAGGGACAUGACAAGACUUCAUUGUCAUUAUCAGUGGUGAUCACAGUAGUUCUAAGGGUAUGUCUUAUGCUUCUGGGCUUUUAACUGCUUCAAAACCCACAAUGAAAGAAAAAAAAAGCGACUCAAGUGUUGAAGUCAGAUGUUUUGAUACUAAUAUAAAUAAAUCUUUCUCCAAGGAUUUUGUAACCAAUGAACAUACAUCCAUGUUCUGGUAGUUGUGGGUUUUUUUGUUUGUUUUUUUGGUUUUUUUCUGUUUGUUUUUGAGACAGACUCUUGCGACCAGGCUGGAGAUUUUCCAUCAACUCCUUACUUCCCCUGUCAGCCUGGGUUCUCCCAGCCUUAGGAGCCACAUGAAUCUAUGGAAAACAAAAAACUAAAACAAGAAAAAAACCAGAAGGCCUCAUUGAAAGCUCUUCAUGCUCAACCACAACCCUAGUUUCCUCUCUCUACUUCUCAGAAUCUCGGUUCACUUAUCUCCUCUGCAAACUAACUUCCAACCCAACUGGUAACAAGAACUACCAGAAUGGAAAAACCUGAGGUUGAAAAUAUCCCUACCAAAAGCAAACCUGCAUGGGAUUUCCUGAAAGUCACAAAAUCAGACAAUGGAAAACCCAGGCAUCUUCACAAUCUAGUAUGUUCUCACCAGGCCAUAUGGUCUGAGUCUUAGAAAUUUUUUCUUUUCAAUAAGCAGUCAUCCUUACUUUCCCUCAAGAUGACAAACAGUUCGUUCUUCUGCCCAGUUUAUAAAGAUCUGGAGCCAUUCACGUAUUUUUUUUAUUUAGUUUUCCUUGUUGGAAUUAUUGGAAGUUGUUUUGCAACCUGGGCUUUUAUACAGAAGAAUACGAAUCACAGGUGUGUGAGCAUCUACUUAAUUAAUUUGCUUACAGCCGAUUUCCUGCUUACUCUGGCAUUACCAGUGAAAAUUGUUGUUGACUUGGGUGUGGCACCUUGGAAGCUGAAGAUAUUCCACUGCCAAGUAACAGCCUGCCUCAUCUAUAUCAAUAUGUAUUUAUCAAUUAUCUUCUUAGCAUUUGUCAGCAUUGACCGCUGUCUUCAGCUGACACACAGCUGCAAGAUCUACCGAAUACAAGAACCCGGAUUUGCCAAAAUGAUAUCAACCGUUGUGUGGCUAAUGGUCCUUCUUAUAAUGGUGCCAAAUAUGAUGAUUCCCAUCAAAGACAUCAAGGAAAAGUCAAAUGUGGGUUGUAUGGAGUUUAAAAAGGAAUUUGGAAGAAAUUGGCAUUUGCUGACAAAUUUCAUAUGUGUAGCAAUAUUUUUAAAUUUCUCAGCCAUCAUUUUAAUAUCCAAUUGCCUUGUAAUUCGACAGCUCUACAGAAACAAAGAUAAUGAAAAUUACCCAAAUGUGAAAAAGGCUCUCAUCAACAUACUUUUAGUGACCACGGGCUACAUCAUAUGCUUUGUUCCUUACCACAUUGUCCGAAUCCCGUAUACCCUCAGCCAGACAGAAGUCAUAACUGAUUGCUCAACCAGGAUUUCACUCUUCAAAGCCAAAGAGGCUACACUGCUCCUGGCUGUGUCGAACCUGUGCUUUGAUCCUAUCCUGUACUAUCACCUCUCAAAAGCAUUCCGCUCAAAGGUCACUGAGACUUUUGCCUCACCUAAAGAGACCAAGGCUCAGAAAGAAAAAUUAAGAUGUGAAAAUAAUGCAUAAAAGACAGGAUUUUUUGUGCUACCAAUUCUGGCCUUACUGGACCAUAAAGUUAAUUAUAGCUUUGAAAGAUAAAAAAAAAAAAAACAAAAAAAAACUCAGUAUGAAAAAAUACAGUUAGCUAGCAAAUAUGGACAGGUUUACUUAGAAAUCCUGUUUCUAAAUGCAAGUCAAGCUUUAUUGUUAGGCUUGCUGCUACUCAUUAACCCAAAUAUUUGUACAAAAAACUAAAGAGUCUCAUUGAACGAAUGUAAAAUCCUGCAAUAUCCUUGAAAUCCAAAAGAGGUCCAUGACAUAGACCCAAAGGUAUUCAUGAGUUAUUCAUUUAAAUGCCUGGAACUGACUUCUUGAUAAAAAUAUAAAAAAUAAUUUCCAUGUAAGUUACCAGAAAGCCCACCAGCAACAUAAUUUUAAAGCCUUUCAGAUUACUUUUAAAAAAUGCAGCUUACAUAUAACAACUUGUGCCUAUUUUAUUUCUAAUCUAUCACUUCAAAAGAUGGUAAUCUUUCAACUCAUUAUUCCUCCAAUUUUUAAUGUCGAAUUUUUUUCUAACACAAUAACCAAAAGCUUUUAUUUAUAAAAAGGCUUGAAAAAUAUA